GGAGACGCACCGGAGCGCUCGCCCAGCCGCCGCCUCCAAGCCCCUGAGGUUUCCGGGGACCACAAUGAACAACUUGCUGUGCUGCGCGCUCGUGUUUCUGGACAUCUCCAUUAAGUGGACCACCCAGGAAACGUUUCCUCCAAAGUACCUUCAUUAUGACGAAGAAACCUCUCAUCAGCUGUUGUGUGACAAAUGUCCUCCUGGUACCUACCUAAAACAACACUGUACAGCAAAGUGGAAGACCGUGUGCGCCCCUUGCCCUGACCACUACUACACAGACAGCUGGCACACCAGUGACGAGUGUCUAUACUGCAGCCCCGUGUGCAAGGAGCUGCAGUACGUCAAGCAGGAGUGCAAUCGCACCCACAACCGCGUGUGCGAAUGCAAGGAAGGGCGCUACCUUGAGAUAGAGUUCUGCUUGAAACAUAGGAGCUGCCCUCCUGGAUUUGGAGUGGUGCAAGCUGGAACCCCAGAGCGAAAUACAGUUUGCAAAAGAUGUCCAGAUGGGUUCUUCUCAAAUGAGACGUCAUCUAAAGCACCCUGUAGAAAACACACAAAUUGCAGUGUCUUUGGUCUCCUGCUAACUCAGAAAGGAAAUGCAACACACGACAACAUAUGUUCCGGAAACAGUGAAUCAACUCAAAAAUGUGGAAUAGAUGUUACCCUGUGUGAGGAGGCAUUCUUCAGGUUUGCUGUUCCUACAAAGUUUACGCCUAACUGGCUUAGUGUCUUGGUAGACAAUUUGCCUGGCACCAAAGUAAACGCAGAGAGUGUAGAGAGGAUAAAACGGCAACACAGCUCACAAGAACAGACUUUCCAGCUGCUGAAGUUAUGGAAACAUCAAAACAAAGACCAAGAUAUAGUCAAGAAGAUCAUCCAAGAUAUUGACCUCUGUGAAAACAGCGUGCAGCGGCACAUUGGACAUGCUAACCUCACCUUCGAGCAGCUUCGUAGCUUGAUGGAAAGCUUACCGGGAAAGAAAGUGGGAGCAGAAGACAUUGAAAAAACAAUAAAGGCAUGCAAACCCAGUGACCAGAUCCUGAAGCUGCUCAGUUUGUGGCGAAUAAAAAAUGGCGACCAAGACACCUUGAAGGGCCUAAUGCACGCACUAAAGCACUCAAAGACGUACCACUUUCCCAAAACUGUCACUCAGAGUCUAAAGAAGACCAUCAGGUUCCUUCACAGCUUCACAAUGUACAAAUUGUAUCAGAAGUUAUUUUUAGAAAUGAUAGGUAACCAGGUCCAAUCAGUAAAAAUAAGCUGCUUAUAACUGGAAAUGGCCAUUGAGCUGUUUCCUCACAAUUGGCGAGAUCCCAUGGAUGAGUAAACUGUUUCUCAGGCACUUGAGGCUUUCAGUGAUAUCUUUCUCAUUACCAGUGACUAAUUUUGCCACAGGGUACUAAAAGAAACUAUGAUGUGGAGAAAGGACUAACAUCUCCUCCAAUAAACCCCAAAUGGUUAAUCCAACUGUCAGAUCUGGAUCGUUAUCUACUGACUAUAUUUUCCCUUAUUACUGCUUGCAGUAAUUCAACUGGAAAUUAAAAAAAAAAAACUAGACUCCAUUGUGCCUUACUAAAUAUGGGAAUGUCUAACUUAAAUAGCUUUGAGAUUUCAGCUAUGCUAGAGGCUUUUAUUAGAAAGCCAUAUUUUUUUCUGUAAAAGUUACUAAUAUAUCUGUAACACUAUUACAGUAUUGCUAUUUAUAUUCAUUCAGAUAUAAGAUUUGUACAUAUUAUCAUCCUAUAAAGAAACGGUAUGACUUAAUUUUAGAAAGAAAAUUAUAUUCUGUUUAUUAUGACAAAUGAAAGAGAAAAUAUAUAUUUUUAAUGGAAAGUUUGUAGCAUUUUUCUAAUAGGUACUGCCAUAUUUUUCUGUGUGGAGUAUUUUUAUAAUUUUAUCUGUAUAAGCUGUAAUAUCAUUUUAUAGAAAAUGCAUUAUUUAGUCAAUUGUUUAAUGUUGGAAAACAUAUGAAAUAUAAAUUAUCUGAAUAUUAGAUGCUCUGAGAAAUUGAAUGUACCUUAUUUAAAAGAUUUUAUGGUUUUAUAACUAUAUAAAUGACAUUAUUAAAGUUUUCAAAUUAUUUUUUA